GUAAAAGUCUGGGCUACCGGCGCGGCGUAGUGGAUGCAGCAUCCUAGUGGAGGACGCCCCUGUGGCUGGAGUGCAAUGGCGCGAUAUCGGCUCGCCGCAACUUCUGCCUCCUGGGUUCAAGUGAAUCUCCUGCCCCAGCCUCCUGAGCAGCUGGGAUGACAGAUGGAGUCUCACUCUGUUGCCCAGGCUGGAGUACAGUGGCGUGAUCUCGGCUCACUGCAAGCUCUGCCUCCCGGACAGCGUCUCAGUCUAACAUCCAGGCUGGAGUGCACUGGCAUGAUCUCAGCUCACUGCAACCUCCGCCUCCCAUAUUCAAGCAGUCCCCCCACCUCAGCCUCCUGAGUAGCUGGGACUGCAUAUGUGCACUGCCACGCCCCGCUAAUUAUUGUAUUGUUUAUAGAGACAGGCUGGGCAACUGCUGGGCUCGAACAGUCCUCCUGCCUCAGCCUCCUAGGGUGUUAGGAUUACAGGCGUGAGCCACUGUGCUUGGCCCCUUGUAAUAUCUCUGUCAGGUUUUCGGUUUGGGUUUUGCUGGCCUCAUUAAGACAGACUGGAUAGCGUCUGCUCUUCCUCUGUUCACUAAAUAGCUUCUAAGAUCAGUACUGUGCUUCCGUAGGCUUUGGUGGAGUUUACCAGGGAAUCCAGCUGGGUGUGGUAUUUUCUGUGUGGGAAGGGUUCCAGUUACAUUUUCAAUUGCCUUAUCAGAUGGAAGGCUUCCCUUUCUUUUGUCAGUUUCAUGAUACUGUGUUUUUCAUCGAGUUUGUCUGUUUCAUCUCAGUUGCUGAACCUGUUUGCAUGAGUUGCUCCUGACGGCCCUUUAGGAUACUUCCAUGUCUGUAGGGUCUAGAGUGACAUCUCCUCCCCUCCCCUGACGAGAUCUGCCCUCCUUGGCACUGUGCUUCCCCAGAGGGGUGGCCUCGCUGUUCCCAUGGACAUGGCCCAGGAGCCAGUGACCUUCAGGGACGUGGCCAUCUACUUCUCAAGGGAGGAGUGGGCGUGUCUGGAACCCAGCCAGAGGGCCCUCUACCGGGACGUGAUGCUGGACAACUUCAGCAGUGUGGCUGCUCUGGGAUUUUGCAGCCCCAGACCAGACCUCGUCUCUCGCCUGGAACAGUGGGAGGAGCCGUGGGUUGAAGACCGGGAGAGACCUGAGUUCCAGGCAGUGCAGAGGGGACCCCGGCCAGGGGCAAGGAAGUCUGCAGACCCCAAGAGACCUUGUGAUCAUCCAGCUUGGGCUCACAAGAAAACCCACGUGCGGCGAGAAAGAGCCAGGGAAGGAAGCAGCUUUAGGAAGGGCUUCAGGCUGGACACGGAUGACGGGCAGCUUCCCAGAGCUGCUCCAGAAAGGACAGACGCCAAGCCCACGGCUUUCCCGUGUCAGGUGCUCACGCAGCGUUGUGGGCGGCGGCCGGGCCGCAGAGAGCGCCGGAAGCAGCGCGCAGUAGAGCUGUCAUUCAUCUGCGGCACGUGCGGGAAGGCGCUCAGCUGCCACAGCCGGCUGCUCGCUCACCAGACGGUGCACACGGGAACCAAGGCCUUCGAGUGCCCCGAGUGCGGCCAGACCUUCCGGUGGGCUUCAAACCUGCAGCGCCACCAGAAGAACCACACGCGCGAGAAGCCCUUCUGCUGCGAGGCCUGCGGGCAGGCGUUCAGCCUGAAGGACCGCCUGGCUCAGCACCGCAAGGUCCACACCGAGCACAGGCCCUACUCGUGUGGCGACUGUGGGAAAGCCUUCAAGCAGAAGUCCAACCUUCUCAGACACCAGCUGGUGCACACCGGGGAGCGGCCGUUCUACUGCGCGGACUGCGGCAAAGCCUUCCGGACCAAGGAGAACCUCAGCCACCACCAGAGGGUCCACAGCGGGGAGAAGCCCUACACCUGUGCCGAGUGCGGCAAGUCCUUCCGGUGGCCCAAGGGCUUCAGCAUCCACCGGAGGCUGCACCUGACGAAGAGGUUCUACGAGUGCGGCCACUGUGGGAAAGGCUUCCGUCACCUGGGGUUCUUCACGCGGCAUCAGAGGACUCACAGGCACGGGGAGGUGUAGGGGCGCCCGAAGAGUGGGGUGCUGCGCCUCUGCGGGAGUACUGGGUCCUGAGGGAGAGCUGCAGUGAGAAGUUGCUCUUCAGCCUGGAAAAUCAACCUGAAUUCAGAGAAGCCUUCUUAGUCCUCAGAGCUCCCCAGUCCCCCGAGAAGUUUACUGGGAAAACUGCCAGGUGGGAGAAGCAGAGCCAUGGGUACGCCGGAGAUGGCGGGGGCUCUGGAGAUGGCGGGGGCUGCGCCCCGGCGCCGGGCAUCCUGGGGAUGUGCUGAGAGUGUGCGCGACCCCGGAGCCACGUGCCAGGCCGGGCUCAGAGGCGGAGAAGCCUGCCUGGUGCCCACAGCCGUCUGGCUCAGGGACUCCACCCUGGCCCCGAGUCGCCGUCUGCUGGGCCUUUCCUUCCUGGCUCUGCACCCCAUGCUGGCUGCCCGGUCUGGCUUCCCUUCUUGUCUCUGUCUUGGGCGAGGCAGCUGUGAGCAUUGCACAGAGGCAAAGACCCUCCUGCAGCCUCUGCGCUGGGCCGUAGAAACAAGAGCCUUUGUAAUACUGAACCUCAUUCAAGGAUUAGGAGUGGUGGUUAGGUCAGGGCCACCCCCAGUGCUGCAGGAACGGCCUCCACCCAGCUCUGUUGGUCAGAGCCUGGGUCAUGCACCUGGAGUUGGGAGAUCAAGUUGGGUCUCAGGGCAGUGAGGUGGCCAUAUCCACCACAUCGCAUUUCGUGGGGGAAGAGGUGACCUCUUUGUUUUAAACUUAAGGUGUCUGCUUAUCCAGCCAGAAAUAAAAAUCUGCCAGUGGUGUUCCCAAGGGAAGACCCCCGUGGGAAUGGGUCGGGACACUGCCGUGUUUCAGGUUAGCCAAUUA